AGGCCCGCUCCCCGAGCCCUGCCAACCAUGGUGAACUUGGGUCUGUCCCGGGUGGACGACGCCGUGGCUGCCAAGCACCCGGGACUCGGGGAGUAUGCCGCAUGCCAGUCACACGCCUUCAUGAAGGGCGUUUUCACCUUCGUCACAGGCACCGGCAUGGCCUUUGGCUUGCAGAUGUUCAUUCAGAGGAAGUUUCCAUACCCUUUGCAGUGGAGCCUCCUAGUGGCCGUGGUUGCAGGCUCUGUGGUCAGCUACGGGGUGACGAGAGUGGAGUCGGAGAAAUGCAACAACCUCUGGCUCUUCCUGGAGACCGGGCAGCUCCCCAAAGACAGGAGCACAGAUCAGAGAAGCUAGGAGAGCUCCAGCAGGGGCACAGAGGAUUGGGGGCAGGAGGAGUCUGGAACACAGCCUUCAUGCCCCCUGACCCCAGGCCGACCCUCCCCACACCCUAGGGUACCCCAGUCGUAUCCUCUGUCCGCAUGUGUGGCCAGGCCUGACAAACACCUGCAGAUGGCUGCUGCCCCAACCUGGGACCUGCCCAGGAGGUUGGAGCAGAAAGGGCUCUCCCUGGGGUGGUGUUUCUCCUCUAGGGUAUUGGGAUGCAUGUUCUGCACUGCCAGCAGAGAGGGUGUGUCUGGGGGCCACCACCUAUGGGACACGGGGUCGAAGGGGCCUGUACACUCUGUCAUUUCCUUUCUAGCCCCUGCAUCUCCAACAAGUCCAAGGUGACAGCUGGUGCUAGGGGCGUGGGGUUAAUAAAUGGCUUAUCCUUCUCUCCACCCAAGUUUCCACCUGACCAGGUGAAAAACAAAUCAGAAGGGUAAGAUGAUGACAGGUCA